CUUUUGGGACACGGCAGGCCAGGAGCGGUUCCAGAGCAUGCAUGCCUCCUACUACCACAAGGCCCAUGCCUGCAUCAUGGCCCUGCUUCAAUGCCACCACCUCCGUGCAGCCUCCUCUGAUGUUUGUCAUUAGCUUAGCUCUUCCGUGUGUGCUCCUGCACCACUGAUCCCUUCCACAACAUGGACUGUCUGUGAUGCACGUGUGCAGGAUGCUGGGAAUGCCCAGGUGGAAAGACACACGUGCUGCCCCCAGGAACUGACUGACUGGUAGGCACAGUACAGAUACCAGUGGUGAGGACAGUGAGGAUUCUUCCCUUCUGACCCUUUGCAGAUGGUAAAGGAAGGAACUCGUCACCUAAUUCCCCCGACUGCCCGUUAAGAACAAAAUCCCUUGAAAAAUUCCAAAAGCUUUAACUCUGAUAACUGUUAAGGUACUAAACAAGAGGAUAAUGGGGCAAGGAAAAUGGGGGCAGUGUAGUGCAGAAGUCUGACCCUCAAGAGCAGAGGAGCUUGGUCCUAGCCAGUUUGGUUUCAGGCCUACAGUGGCAUUUGGUAUUUUGAGCUCACCUCUCUUUUUCUCUUGGAGUGACUGCUUCCUGCAUCUGCUGCAUCUCCGUGGGCUCCCCUCAGACCCUCUUCUGAAGGCCUGGGGUGUCUCUCCUGCCACCAUGCCUGUGUCUGCAGGUGCCUGCCACCAGCCCCAGUCUGCUGCACGGGCCCUGGCAAGUAGAAAGCACUUGCCUUCUGACCACACGGGGAGCUGAGGGUCAGAGACGGAACCAGGGCUCGACCCUCCACCUUGAAACCUUGAGAUGGGGAUGCUCCUCAUUCUAGCCAGUUCCUCCUCAGCUCUCAAAACAAGGAACAGAUGCUCAGGAAACCAGAUCUGGACAAAAGUCAUCUGAGCCUGGUGUGAGGCAGAUUCCAGAAGUUUAGUUACAGACAUCCUUUAUAAGGAGACUUCAUCGGGAAUUCAAGACAACCUGGUGAUUCAUUGAAAUUUGCCUGUGAAAGAGAAUCUACAUAGACUUCCUGCCACCUCUUGAGAUGUGACAGUUGCUGACCCUCCCGCCACCACACAGGGCGAGCCCCUAGCCCUGAGCUUGAACCAUGUUGCUUGCACAAAUAGCUGGGUGAUUUAGAAGUGAGGUCAGCUGUGCCAGCAGUUACAGGGUGGUGGUUGUCUGUAACUUUAAUCCACUGACUGUUGUACUAGGGCAGUUUGGGCUAGACACUUUGGAGGAGCUCCUGUGAAGGGCAUGAAGGCUCACUGUAGCAGCAGCUCAGUUGUCUUUCAGAGUUCUGCCCUUAGAGCUGGUUUGCAGUGCUCAUCCUUCUUGCUGAUAUUUUAAAAUAGGUAGAAACAGGCUGGGCGCGGUGACUCAUGCCUUUAAUCCCAGUACUUUGGGAGGCCUAGGUGGGCAGAUCACCUGAGGUCAGGAGUUCGAGACCAGCCUGACCAACAUGUUGAAACCCCGUCUCUACUAGAAAUACAAAAAUUAGCCAGGCGUGGUGGCGCGCACCUGUAAUCCAGCUACUCAGGAGGCUGAGACAGGAGAAUCGUUUGAAGACAGGAGAAUCGUUUGAACCCAGGAGGUGGAGGUUGCAGUGGCAGUGAGCCAAGAUACCGCCACUGCACUCUAGCCUGGGCAACAGAGCAAGACUCCAUCUCAAAAUAAAUAAAUAAAUAAAAAUAAAAUAGGUAAAAACAAAUUAUAAAGUAAUACAAUUAUGAACUGCAAAUAAUAAAACAUAAAAAUUACUUUAAAAAAAUUUAAAGAGGCCGGGCACAGUGGCUUAUGCCUGUAAUCCCAGAAAUUUGGGAGGCCGAGGCAGGAGGAUCACUUGAGCCCGGGAGUCCAAGACCAGCCUCGUUAAUAUAAUGAGAGCUUAUCAUCUCUACAAAAAAUAAACAAAAUUAGCCAGGCAUGGUGGCAUGUGCCUGUAGUUCCAGCUACUCAGGAGGCUGAGGUAGGAGGAUCACUGGAGCCCAGGGGGUGGAGGAGCAGUAAGCCAAGAUUCUGCCACUGCACUCCAGCCUGGCUGACAGAGUAAGACCCUAUCUCAAAAAACAAAAAGCAGAAAGAACAAAGAAGUAAACAAAAGCUUAAAAGUAAAUCAGCCAGGUGCAGUAGCUCAUGCCUGUAAUCCCAGUACUUUGGGAGGCCUAGGCAGGCAGAUUACUGCAGGUCAAGAGUUUGAGACCAGCCUGGCCAACAUGAUGAAACCCUGUCUCUACUAAAACUACAAAAAUUAGCCAGGCAUGGUGGUGCGCACCUGUAAUCCCAGCUACUCCGGAGGCUGAGACAAGAGAAUCGCUUGAACCUAGGAAGUGGAGGUUGCAGUGGCAGUGAGCCAAGAUAGCGCCACUGCACUCCAGCCUGGGCAACAGAGCAAGACUCCAUAUAUGGAGAUCCCUUGAGAUCAAGAGUUCGAGACCAGCCUGGCCAACACGGCAAAACCCUGUCUCUACUAAAAAUAAAAAAAUUAGCCAGGCAUGGUGGCGCACACCUGUAGUCCCAGCUACUGAGGAGGCUGAGACAAGAGAAUCACUUGAACACAGAAGGCAAAGGUUGCAGUGAGCUGAGAUUAUGCCACCACACUCCAGCCUGGGUAACAGAGUGAGACUCCGUCUAAAAAAAAAAAAAAAUCGGGCAGUUGUGAUGGCUAACACCUGUAACCCCAGCACCUUUAGAGGCCCAGGUGGGAGGAUCCCUUCAGGCCAAGAGUUUGAGAUGAGCCUGGGUAACAUAGGGAGAGCCUGCCUCUACAAAAAAAAAAAUAAUAAAAAAAUAAAAAUUAAUGCGUGCGUGCUACUUGGGAGGCUGAGGUAGGAGGAUUCCUUGAGCCCAGGAGUUUUGAGGUUACAGUGAGCUGUGAUUGAGCCACUGCAUUCUAGCCUGGGUGACAGUGAAACCCUGUCUCUAAAAAGUAAAUAAAUAAAAGUAAAUAGUAACUAAAGUAAAACUCUAGAAACAUUUACAGUUACUACAGAGGAACUUUAAAACAGUUUAAGCAAUAAAUACAAGAGGACUAAAAAACACAAAAGUUUUUACAAUUUCUAACAGACUGCAUCAAUUGGCAAAUUGAUUCCAUUUAUGAUUGUUAAAAUAGGUGAAUAAGAUUAGAUGACAAGAUAACAAAAAAGGAAUACGUUAUUUAUUUGUUUAUUUCAGACAGAGUUUUGCUCUUGUUGCCCAGGCUGGAGUGCAAUGGCAUGAUCUGGGCUCACUGCAACCUCUGUCUCCCUAGUUCAAGCAAUUCUCCUGCCUCAGCCUCCCAAGUAGCUGAGAUUACCGGCAUGCGCCACCACGCCCAGCUAAUUUUUUGCAUUUUUAGUAGAGACGGAAUUUCACCAUGUUGGCCAGGCUGGUCUCAAACUCCUGACCUCAGGUGAUUGACCCGCCUCAACCUCCCAAAGUGCUGGGAUUACAGGUGUGAGCCACUGCACUGGGCCAAGAAUAAGAUUUUUAAAAACAUUUUCGCAUCUGGAGGCUCCAGGGGGCUUCCCUGAGAAACGGCAGCCUCUGCGGUCAGAGAGGCUGCAAUUCAGAGCGUUCCCACAAACAGCACCAUGUGCUCAUGCUUACCUGCUUGGGUGUGUGAGUCACCUGGAGAUGGGGUGCAGAAACAUUGACAUACCUGAGCUAUCUUUCUUCCUCUGCCCUUUGCAGGUGUUUGAUAUACAGAGGAAAGUCACCUAUAGGAACCUGAGCACCUGGUAUACAGAGCUUCGGGAGUUCAGGCCAGAGAUCCCAUGCAUCGUGGUGGCCAAUAAAAUUGAUGCAGACAUAAACGUGACCCAAAAAAGCUUCAAUUUUGCCAAGAAGUUCUCCCUGCCCCUGUAUUUCGUCUCGGCUGCUGAUGGUACCAAUGUUGUGAAGGUGUGGUUGACUGCAGAGGUAGCUAGCAAGCUCUUCAAUGAUGCAAUUCGAUUAGCUGUGUCUUACAAACAGAACUCCCAGGACUUCAUGGAUGAGAUUUUUCAGGAGCUCGAGAACUUCAGCUUGGAGCAGGAAGAGGAGGACGUGCCAGACCAGGAACAGAGCAGCAGCAUCGAGACCCCAUCAGAGGAGGUGGCCUCUCCCCACAGCUGAGGGGCUGGGGCUAGGGGUGGGUGGAGCCCUUUUAAAAUACCCUUCCCUUCAACAACUCUCCAGCUCUGAAUGGAGAAACUCUCUAGGCCAUCCCCUCUUCUACCUCCUGCAACCCACCCAUCCUAUUAGCCUCCCACAUUCAAGGCCCGUGAUACAGGGAUGAGGUCAGCACCAGCAAACUCUGGACUGGUGGAAGAAUUCCCCACCAGAUCUCCUUGAAGCAGAAUUAGGGAUCAGCAUCAUUAACACCUUCCCCACCCCCUCCCCCCAGGCAGACAGUGAAGAGAAUCAGAAAACAUGAUUAUGUGUCACUUUAAUACAGGAAAUUUAGGUGUUUUUUGGUGUUUUUGUUUUUGUUUUCUUUCCAAAGCUCACCUCGGGGACAAUUCCUUGGGCUUCUCCUGAGGUAAUGAUUACCCCCCCACCCACAGCUGAGUCUGUGAGGCCCCAUCCUUUCCCUACGUUUUCUCCCAUCUUUUUUCCUCUUCAAUCUCCCAGUCAUCUGGUUUGUUUGUUUCUUUGUUCGUCCUGAGACGGAGUCUCGCUCUGUCGCCAGGCUGGAGUGCAGUGGCGCAGUCUCGGCUCGCUGCAACCUCUGACUCCCUGGUUCAAACGAUUCUCCUGCCUCAGCCUCCCGAGUGGCUGGCAUCACCACGCCCAGCUAAUUUUUGUAUUUUUAGUAGAGACGGGGUUUCACCAUGUUGCCCAGGAUGGUCUCGAUCUCCUCACCUCGUGAUCCGCCCGCCUCGGCCUCCCAAAGUGCUGGGAUUACAGGCAUGAGCCACCGCGCCCGGCCCCAAUCAUCUGUUUUUAAACAAUCGUUUUUGAGCAGAUAGCUAUUCAUUCCAGAUUUCCGUGUACCCACUCUGUUUCAGGAGCUCUUCUAGGUAAAGCUGAGAUCACAGGAACAGCAGGUGACAGGCCUAGCUAUAGUUAGGAAUACACAAGCGGUAAAAUCGAGUCCUUACAGCCAUACCACAAGGUACGUCCAUUUGGACUACAAGAAGAGCUUCCUUUAAAGUUCCUAUUUCAGCAUAAAGAGGCUGUCCUUUUUUUUUAGGAAUAGUUUGGACCUUGUGCCUCCUGUGGGAGGCUGAGGACUGCAAGAGGAGAGCUAGCAGAUAUGCCUGUUCACCCCUCUCUGGUACUUGUGGCUUGCUAGUAUGUUUUUAUGAUAAUCUCGGGCAUUGUUUGCAUUGUGUUUAUUAAUAGGGUUUUGUUUUUAUUGUUUCCUUUUUUACAGUAAAGGCUGAAUGACAUAAA